AUGAAUACCACUCUAUUUCAUCCUUACUCUUUCCUUCUUCUGGGAAUUCCUGGGCUGGAAAGUAUGCAUCUCUGGGUUGGUUUUCCUUUCUUUGCUGUGUUCCUGACAGCUGUCCUUGGGAAUAUCACCAUCCUUUUUGUGAUUCAGACUGACAGUAGUCUCCAUCAUCCCAUGUUCUACUUCCUGGCCAUUCUGUCAUCUAUUGACCCGGGCCUGUCUACAUCCACCAUCCCUAAAAUGCUUGGCACCUUCUGGUUUACCCUGAGAGAAAUCUCCUUUGAAGGAUGCCUUACCCAGAUGUUCUUCAUCCACCUGUGCACUGGCAUGGAAUCAGCUGUGCUUGUGGCCAUGGCCUAUGAUUGCUAUGUGGCCAUCUGUGACCCUCUUUGCUACACGUUGGUGCUGACAAACAAGGUGGUGUCAGUUAUGGCACUGGCCAUCUUUCUGAGACCCUUAGUCUUUGUCAUACCCUUUGUUCUAUUUAUCCUAAGGCUUCCAUUUUGUGGACACCAAAUUAUUCCUCAUACUUACGGUGAGCACAUGGGCAUUGCCCGCCUGUCUUGUGCCAGCAUCAGGGUUAACAUCAUCUAUGGCUUAUGUGCCAUCUCUAUCCUGGUCUUUGACAUCAUAGCAAUUGUCAUUUCCUAUGUACAGAUCCUUUGUGCUGUAUUUCUACUCUCUUCACAUGAUGCACGACUCAAGGCAUUCAGCACCUGUGGCUCUCAUGUGUGUGUCAUGUUGACUUUCUAUAUGCCUGCAUUUUUCUCAUUCAUGACCCAUAGGUUUGGUCGGAAUAUACCUCACUUUAUCCACAUUCUUCUGGCUAAUUUCUAUGUAGUCAUUCCACCUGCUCUCAACUCUGUAAUUUAUGGUGUCAGAACCAAACAGAUUAGAGCACAAGUGCUGAAAAUGUUUUUCAAUAAAUAA